UUCCUUUAUAAAUUAUGCAGUCUCUGGUAUUUCUUCACAGUAGCGUGAGAAUGGACAAAUACAUAAGGAGAGAGUAUUUUCCUCAUUGUACACUCAGAGAUAUUGUACCUGGCAUGUUACAGUGCAGAUUUUAUUCCACGGAGGUGCUUUGAACUAAUCUGAGUUUUCUUUGCAGUUAUUGAUUGGUAAACAGUUAUUUAAAUUUUUUUUUUUUUUUCGAGAAGGAUUCUUGCUCUGUCACCCAGGCUGUGGUGUGAUCUUGGCUCACUGCAACCUCCAUCACCCGGGUUCGCAGUGUUGAACAGGCUGGUCUCGAACUCCUGACCUCAAGUGAUCCACUUGCCUCGGCCUUCCAAAAUGCUAGGAUUACAGGCAUGAGCCACAAUGCCUGGCCUAAAUUUGGUUUUAUUCUCCUGUAUAUGUUUUUCCUUUGAUUACUGUAUUUUUAGUUUAAUUGCACUUAUAAAAAUUUUAUUUUUAUUUUUAUUUUUUGAGACGGGAUCUCACUGUGUUGCUCAGGCUGAAGUGCGGUGGUACAGGCUCACUGCAGCCUUGACCUCCUAGGCUCAAGUGAUUCUCCCACCUCAGCCCCCUGAAUAGCUGGGACUAUAGGCACAUACCACCCCACCUGGUUAAAUUAAAAAAAAAAUUUUUUUAGGGAUUACAUCUCUUUUGUUGCCCAGGCAGAUUUCAGACUCCUGGGCUCAAAGCAAUUCUCCCGCCUCAGCCUCCCAAAGUGCUGGGAUAACAGAUGUGAGCCAGCAGGUCCAGCCUAAUUGCACUUUUAAGUCUUAGACUGAAAACUUUAUGAAAUCCUAUCUUCAUCACUAUAUGUCUUGUUUUCUGUUUUAUUUUGUUCUUUCAUUGACCCUGAUAUUUGGAAAAAUUCUAAUGCUUUUAUAAGUUCUUUGAUCUAAUUGUUUCAAGUCUUCUGUUUCCUGAAAUUAUUAACUAUCUUUAAAGAGAAAAGUCAUCUUGGCUAUAUGCUGUGGUUGUCAAGGUGGCGUCAGCUCUGAGCAAAUAUUUUUCCAAGCUUGCAAGCUUGAGUAUUCUCAAGUCUGAGGUCAUGCUCAUCUAUUUAUAUUUAAAUAUUUAUUCUUUCUUCCUGGCAGUAUAUGAAAUAUUUUUAUUUUUAUUUAUUAUUAUUAUUUUUUUGAGACAGAGUCUUGCUGUGUCGCCCAGGCUGGAGUGCAGUGGUGCAAUCUCGGCUUACUGCAACCUCCACCUCUCAAGUUCAAGCAAUUCUCCUGCCUCAGCCUCCCGAGUAGCUGGGACUACAGGCGCCCGCCACUAAGCCCAGCUCAUUUUUUUUGUAUUUUGUUGUAGAGGUGAGGUUUCACUGUGUUAGCCAGGAUGGUCUCGAUCUCUGACCUCGUGAUGCGCCCACCUCGGCCUCAAAGUGCUGGGAUUAUAGGCGUGAGCCACCACGCCUGGCGAAAUAUUUUUAUUUUUAUCCUUUAAAAAUUUUUCUCUUAAAGCUUUUUUUUUUCUUUUUUUUUUUUUUUGUGAGUUAGAGUCUUGCUCUAUCACUGUUGGAGUGCAAGUGGCAUGAUCUCAGUUCACUGCAACGUCCACCUCCCAUGUUCAGGCGAUUCUCGCCUCAGCCUAUCAUGUAGCUAGGAUUACAGGUGUGCACCACCACGCCCAGCUAAUUUUUGUAUUUUUGGUAGAGGUGGGGUUUCACUGUGUUAGCCAGGAUGGUCUCAAAUUCCUUACCUCAGGUGAUCCGCCCACUUCAGCCUCUCAAAGUGCUGGGAUUAUAGGCAUGAGCCACCGCACCUGGCCGGUGUUGUUUUUUAAAAUCAUUUUUUUUCUCAUUUAAAGUAUUUGCUUUUAACAUAUUUCUGUCCUGGUACAGUGGCUCAUGCCUGUAGUCAUAGCACUUGAGGAGGCUGAGGGGGAAGAUUGCUUGAGGCAGGAGUUUGAGACCACCCUGGGCAAAAUAGCAAGACCCCUGUCUUUAAAAAUAAAAUUAAAAGUUAGCUGUGUGCCUGUAGUCCUAGCUACUAGGGAGGCUGAGUUGGGAGGAUUGCUUGAGCCCAAGAGUGUGAGGUUACAGUGAGGUGUGAUUGUGCCACUGCACUCCAGUCUGGGUGCAGAGUGAGACCCUGUCUCUAAAAACAAAAAUAAACAUGUUUCUUAUUACUUGAAAUGUUUGGCUGCAGUUUAAGAGCUGGCCAUUUUGGGUCAUUUCUCUGAAUCUCUGAAUUUCUCUGAAUCUCCUGCUGGUUUGUUUUUCUUUUUCCUGAGAGUGAGUAUUUGUAUGAGGGUGUUGGUUGUUUUUAAGAUAAAAUUUUUGAUUUUGGUAGCUAGAGAGACAUAGGUAUAAAAAUUUAGAACUGGAAGAGACUGUAGAAGUCAUAUAUUCUAAUAUAUUUGAAUUACAGAUGGGUAAAUGAUACUUGGGUAGUUGAAACAAGUUGAUUAUGGACCCAUAGCUUAGCAGUAGAUGUAUGGGGAGAAAAAGUAGUUAUUUUUUCCUCAUCCAUUGCUAGGUUCAUGGCUGAGACCACUACAGCAAAGGGCAGAUUAGUGAGAAGAACAUACAAAUUUAUUUAAGUUUUAUGUGACAUGGAGCCUUCAGAAAUGAAGACCCAAAUCAACAGGGAAACUUAUGUAAUUUUAUGGGUUAGGUUUGAUGGAGAGUGGACAGCGUGUAGAAGUCUGAUGGACAGAGGGAGAAUGAUCUAAUGAUAAUAACCUGGGGGGAACUUAGCAAGGCUUGUUUGGUCAUAGUCUUCUCAAUGUCCCUGUGUCUUCAGAGAUAAGGACAUUCCUUUCCUCUGAGUAAAGGGAGGGUACCUCUGGAAUGAGGGUCUUAUAACCUACUUCAGAGAAGAAGAUGAGAUAAUUCUUCUAUGGUCUGCUUCAGAGGAGAAGGGCUGGAGAAGGUCAGAGAGACCUCUUUGCUUCUGCUGUUUCCUCAAAUGCCAAGGUGCUGUAUUUUGGACUAGUGUGCCCUGAACCCAGUCUUAGAGCACAGAAAGACUAGAAUCUAACCCAUUUUUCUAGAUUUAGUUUCUAGUUAUUUUUUGUUAGUGCCUAUUUUUUGCUUUUGGUAGUAUUAUUACAUCAUUGAGCAUUUAUGUGCCAACAUUUCUGUAAACUUUAUCUCAUUUAAUUCUUAGCUGAUAAAUGAUGAAAACAGUUUUCAGAACAAGGCAUAUAACUCCAAAAAUUACACUCUUAACUGUUGUGCUUUAGUGGUAGAAUGGUUUAGGGAUUGGGUGCUUGUGUGUCAGACACAUUAUCCUACUACUUCAUUUAAUCCUCAGAACUGCUCUAAGAGCUGAACAUACUCUCUGGCUUUACAGACAAGGACAUUUGGCUAAGAGAGAUUGUCUUCUGCCUUCAGACCACACAGCUAGUAGGUUGCAGAGCUUGAUUGUAAGUUUUGUUGUUUCCCAAUUCUCUGCUACAUCUGAGGGGAGAUAUCCCUCAUUGAUAUUCCGGUCUUCCCAAAGCCUUCAUGAUAAUAUGAUAAGAGAAAAAAGCAAAUGUAUACAUGCAGCCAUAAAAAAGAACAAAAUCAUGUCCUUUGCAGCAACAUGGAUGCAGCUGAAGGCCAUUAUCCUAAGUGAAUUAAUGCAGGAACAGAAAACCAAAUACCCUGUGUUCUCACUUAUAAGUGGGAGCUGAGCAUUGAGUACAAAUGGACAUAAAGGUGGGAAUAAUAGACACUGGGAACUAUUAGAGGGGAAGGAAUGGGGGGGGCAAGGGUUGAAAAACCUGUUGGGCACCGUGCUUACUACCUGAGUGACAGGAUUAUUCGUACCCCAAACCUUAGUGACACACAAUUUACCCAUGUGACAAAUCUGCACAUGUACCCCCUGAACUUAAAAGUUGAAAAAAUAUAUAUAUAACAUAUACAAUUCACUUUAUUAAAGGUUAAUAAAUAUAACUGAUUUAUUUUUAGGCUAGUCUUCGUGUACUAUUUUUGUGCCUUUCUCAGAUAUUUUGUGGACUUGAGUCUGAAGUAAAUAUUUAUAAAGGGAAAGUAGAUAACUGCUAUUACCAGGAAAAUACUUAUUCAAAAAAAAAGGAUAUUUAAGAGAUAAUUAGAAUGACUUUACUGACCUUGUUUUCUUACACUAAUAAUUCAUGAAGCAUUUAGAUUUUCUGAUUGAGUGUUUUCUGUGACAAUAUCAGUCAGAGAUGUAAUCAUUUAUAAACAUGCUGUUAAUGGCAUGGACUCUGGUGUCAGUCUGUGUGGGUUUAGAUCCUCUGUUAAAUUUCUGAUUUUGGUAGCUUGACAUAGGUAUAAAAAAAUUUACAACCUGAAGAGACCUUAGAAAUAAUGUAUUCCUGGGCAAGUUAUUCAUUCGCUAUGUGUCCCUUUUCUCACCAGUAAAAUAGGUAUGCUAAUAAUACCUACCUCAUAGAGUUAUGAGAAUUAAGGAAUUAUUACAUGUAAAAUUCUCAGCUAGUGCAUGAUUAAUGGUAAGUACUCAAAAAGUUAUAGCUGUUAUUGUUUUUUAAACAUUAUUUUUUAACAUUUUUAUUGGUUGAAAUAGGUUUCAGACAAUUGUAAAUAAAUUUUAAAAAAUUAAAAAAUGUUAAGGCUGAGAGAAUUUUGAGACCUUAAUACAAGGUAGUAUAUUGUAUCAGGCUUGUUCUGUGCCUAGGCUUAAUUACCAGAUUUCUGUGCUUCUGGACUUAUAAUGUAUAGUUGUCGUUUUAAUGCUAACAUUCUGAUUGGAUACGUCCAGCACUUCACUUGGGUAAAUCACAAUCUUUCUUUCCUCCCUCACAAAGGACACUUUGAAAUGAUCCUAAAAUACCUUCUUAUUCAGAUAGAUAGAACAGCUAGUGGUAGAGGCCCUAACAAAAAAAAAAAAAAGAAAGAAAAGAAUGGAGAAUCAGAGGAGCUGACUUCAGAAGAAGCUUUGCAUCGUCCCUAUGGUUGUGAUGUUGAACCCCAGGCACUAAAUGAGGCUAUCAGGUGGAGCUCCAAGGAGAACUUGCUCGGAGCCACUGAGAGUGACCCUAAUCUCUUCGUUGCACUUUAUGAUUUUGUAGCAAGUGGUGAUAACACACUCAGCAUCACUAAAGGUGAAAAGCUACGAGUCCUUGGUUACAACCAGAAUGGUGAGUGGAGUGAAGUUCGCUCUAAGAAUGGGCAGGGCUGGGUGCCAAGCAACUACAUCACCCCAGUGAACAGCCUGGAAAAACACUCCUGGUACCAUGGACCUGUGUCACGCAGUGCAGCUGAGUAUCUGCUCAGCAGUCUAAUCAAUGGCAGCUUCCUGGUGCGAGAAAGUGAGAGUAGCCCUGGGCAGCUGUCCAUCUCGCUCAGGUACGAGGGACGUGUGUAUCACUACAGGAUCAAUACCACUGCAGAUGGCAAGGUGUAUGUGACUGCUGAGAGCCGCUUCAGCACCUUGGCAGAGCUUGUACACCAUCACUCCACAGUGGCUGAUGGGCUGGUGACAACAUUACACUACCCAGCACCCAAGUGUAAUAAGCCUACAGUCUAUGGUGUGUCCCCCAUCCACGACAAAUGGGAAAUGGAGCGAACAGAUAUUACCAUGAAGCACAAACUUGGGGGCGGUCAGUAUGGAGAGGUUUACGUUGGCGUCUGGAAGAAAUACAGCCUUACAGUUGCUGUGAAAACAUUGAAGGAAGAUACCAUGGAGGUAGAAGAAUUCCUGAAAGAAGCUGCAGUAAUGAAGGAAAUCAAGCAUCCUAAUCUGGUACAACUUUUAGGUGUGUGUACUUUGGAGCCACCAUUUUACAUUGUGACUGAAUACAUGCCAUACGGGAAUUUGCUGGAUUACCUCCGAGAAUGCAACCGAGAAGAGGUGACUGCAGUUGUGCUGCUCUACAUGGCCACUCAGAUUUCUUCUGCAAUGGAGUACUUAGAGAAGAAGAAUUUCAUCCAUAGAGAUCUUGCAGCUCGUAACUGCCUAGUGGGAGAAAACCAUGUGGUAAAAGUGGCUGACUUUGGCUUAAGUAGAUUGAUGACUGGAGACACUUAUACUGCUCAUGCUGGAGCCAAAUUUCCUAUUAAGUGGACAGCACCAGAGAGUCUUGCCUACAAUACCUUCUCAAUUAAAUCUGACGUCUGGGCUUUUGGGGUAUUGUUGUGGGAAAUUGCUACCUAUGGAAUGUCACCAUAUCCAGGUAUUGACCUGUCUCAGGUCUAUGACCUACUAGAAAAAGGAUAUCGAAUGGAACAGCCUGAGGGAUGCCCCCCUAAGGUUUAUGAACUUAUGAGAGCAUGCUGGAAGUGGAGCCCUGCCGAUAGGCCCUCUUUUGCUGAAACACACCAAGCUUUUGAAACCAUGUUCCAUGACUCCAGCAUUUCUGAAGAGGUAGCUGAGGAGCUUGGGAGAGCCGCCUCCUCGUCAUCUGUUGUUCCAUACCUGCCCCGGCUACCUAUACUUCCUUCCAAGACUCGGACACUGAAGAAACAGGUGGAGAACAAGGAGAACAUUGAAGGGGCACAAGAUGCCACAGAAAAUUCUGCUUCCAGUUUAGCACCAGGGUUCAUCAGAGGUGCACAGGCCUCUAGUGGAUCCCCAGCACUGCCUCGAAAGCAAAGAGACAAGUCACCCAGCAGCCUCUUGGAAGAUGCCAAAGAGACAUGCUUCACCAGGGAUAGGAAGGGGGGCUUCUUCAGCUCCUUCAUGAAGAAGAGAAAUGCUCCUACACCCCCCAAACGCAGCAGCUCCUUCCGAGAAAUGGAGAAUCAGCCCCAUAAGAAAUACGAACUCACGGGUAACUUCUCAUCUGUUGCUUCUCUACAGCAUGCUGAUGGGUUCUCUUUCACUCCUGCCCAGCAAGAGGCGAAUCUGGUGCCACCCAAGUGCUAUGGGGGGAGCUUUGCACAGAGGAACCUCUGUAAUGACGACGGUGGUGGGGGUGGGGGCAGUGGCACUGCUGGGGGUGGGUGGUCUGGCAUCACAGGCUUCUUUACACCACGCUUAAUCAAAAAGACACUGGGCUUACGAGCAGGUAAACCCACAGCCAGUGAUGACACUUCCAAGCCUUUUCCAAGGUCAAACUCUACAUCUUCCAUGUCCUCAGGGCUUCCAGAGCAGGAUAGGAUGGCAAUGACCCUUCCCAGGAACUGCCAGAGGUCCAAACUCCAGCUGGAAAGGACAGUGUCCACCUCUUCUCAGCCAGAAGAGAAUGUGGACAGGGCCAAUGACAUGCUUCCAAAAAAAUCAGAGGAAAGUGCUGCUCCAAGCAGGGAGAGACCAAAAGCCAAGUUAUUGCCCAGAGGAGCCACAGCUCUUCCUCUCAGAACACCCUCUGGGGAUCUAGCCAUUACAGAGAAGGACCCUCCAGGGGUGGGAGUGGCUGGAGUGGCAGCUGCCCCCAAGGGUAAAGAGAAGAAUGGUGGGGCACGACUUGGGAUGGCUGGAGUUCCAGAGGAUGGAGAGCAGCCGGGCUGGCCUUCUCCAGCCAAGGCUGCCCCCGUCCUCCCAACCACUCACAACCACAAAGUGCCAGUCCUUAUCUCACCCACUCUGAAACACACUCCAGCUGACGUGCAGCUCAUUGGCACAGACUCUCAGGGGAAUAAAUUCAAGCUCUUAUCUGAGCAUCAGGUCACAUCCUCUGGAGACAAGGACCGACCCCGACGGGUAAAACCAAAGUGUGCCCCACCCCCACCACCAGUGAUGAGACUACUGCAGCAUCCGUCCAUCUGCUCAGACCCUACAGAAGAGCCAACUGCCCUAACUGCAGGACAGUCCACAUCAGAAACACAGGAAGGAGGAAAGAAGGCAGCUCUGGGCGCAGUGCCCAUCAGUGGGAAAGCUGGGAGGCCAGUGAUGCCUCCACCUCAAGUGCCUCUGCCCACAUCUUCCAUCUCGCCAGCCAAAAUGGCCAAUGGCACAGCAGGUACUAAAGUGGCUCUGAGAAAAACCAAACAGGCCGCUGAGAAAAUCUCAGCAGACAAAAUCAGCAAAGAGGCCCUGCUGGAAUGUGCUGACCUACUGUCCAGUGCACUCACGGAACCUGUGCCCAACAGCCAGCUGGUAGACACUGGACACCAGCUGCUUGACUACUGCUCAGGCUAUGUGGACUGCAUCCCUCAAACUCGCAACAAAUUUGCCUUCCGAGAGGCUGUGAGCAAACUGGAACUCAGCCUGCAGGAGCUACAGGUUUCUUCAGCAGCUGCUGGUGUGCCCGGGACAAACCCUGUCCUUAAUAACUUAUUGUCAUGUGUACAGGAAAUCAGUGAUGUGGUGCAGAGGUAGCCACUGUUAGCCUGGUGGGAAAAUGCACACAUUUCUGAGGGGAGAGGGAAAAGGACUUGUUUUCCUGUGUUCUUGUUUUCAGAAAAUGAAAGACUCAUACUUGAGUGUGUUUAUGUGAAGUACCUCAGAUCCCUGAGUUCUCACGUUUACAGUUUCAUCUCAAAAAUAAGAAGCAAACCACAUAAGUAUAGGAGAGGUAAAUUAAGUGGGGGCAAGGCAGUAGUGGACAGGGUUGGAAACUGCACUGGAAAAUAGGGAACAUGUGUAUGUCAUAAGGAAGGCAAUGCAGCCCAUCCCUACCUGGAAUGCUGGGAAGUGCUAGGCAGGGCUGCUCUCAGCAAGACUGCAGCAGCUGCACCCAGACCUGGGGCUCUGGUAGGUACUAAUGGUGAUUAUGCUCCAAUUUACCUAAUGAAUUUGGUGGGACAGCAGAAAAGAAAGCUGGGAAUGUACCAAGAGAAAUUUUUGUUCAGGGCUGUUGGAAGUAGCUGUUAGCCUUGCUUCCACAAGGCCAUUGCUGCUGUAAUAAGAACUGCAAAUCAGAGUGCUACAACAUAAAACUGGGAAAUAUGGCCCUAUCUGAAUGCCUCUGUCCUAUUUUCCGCUGGUGUAUCAGUUAGUGCAGGAAGUAAAGAAUGCUGGAAAGUUGAAUCAGAAAUUGAAAACCUUCUAAAAUCUUACACAGAUUAGCAGAAGUCACUUCUCCCAGUCUGGUAUAUUAUUUCAUAAUGGACCAGGAUCGGCUUCCUGCCUGUUGGUGGCUAUCUGUAAACCAUAAGUACAGGGGUCUCCCUAGUGGUUCUUCUCUGUCUUUUGCUGGGCAGGCUGUCUUCCUUUAUUCCUGGUAGCAUUCAGAGCAUUAACCAGUGUUGAUUUUGAAAAUAGUAGUCCCUACAGGUUCUCACAAAGGAAUGAAUCCUGUUCUGAUACAGUUCCCCUGCAUACUGACAUACUGGCCAAGGACUUGAGCAGCUGUGUAUUUUUCUUUAUCAACUAAAAUACCAGGGAGAUGGUCUUUUCUUGAAACCCAGUGGCCUGUAUGUGACUGAGAGGAAAAGCUGGCUUGGUCCUAAUGGCUGUUUCUCUGUACCUUUCCCUUCCCUUACCACCUUAAGCCCAAUCCAGGUAGAGAAUAGGGAGAGGCAUUCUCCUCUCUAUGGAUUUGAAGUGAAUCACCCCCACAUUAUUCUCACAUGCUUUUCUUCUCUCACAUAUUCCUCCCUACUCCCCCACCCAAUCAUUGUGCUUAUUUGUACAGAUCUUAUUGGGAAUAUUCUUUAUUUAUUUUGUCAUUUCACUUCUAUUUUAAGAAUGCAUAAUUGAAGGAGUAGUCAUUUUCAGGGAGCACCAGGUAGACCCUGGGAACCUAAUGACUUAAUCCUUAAAUAUGUUUUGCCCUUGAAAAAUAGGCCUUUUCCUUCCUUCCUUAGUUAUAAUUGUGGAAGCUAAUUAGGAUGGCAUGGAAGUGAAUCUAAUGAGUUAGGUAUUAUUAAUGUUCUUGGUAUCGGGUCUAAUUCCAGUUACUGCUUCAUUCUCUUUUUAAAGCUUUAUGAAUACUUCCCCCAUCCUCCCCAAGGAGAGCUCAAUACACACAUAUUUUUAUUUUAUUCUCUCAAAGGAAUAUUAGCUUAGGAAGAUAGGAAUUCAACAUUGAGCACUGAGUUUUCUUCUGGCUCUGUCAUUGAUACACUGUCAAACCACAGCCUCAUCUCUUAAUCUAUUUAAUUAAGGUAACAGUACAUGUUCUCAAGGGUGUUGCAAGUAAGUGUGCAGCUAUCCCUUGGAGAGCCUCUCUGGAAAGCUCUUUUAGUGCAGUGUUGUUAUGCUGAAUUGUUUUCCAUUAUCUUAUUUGCUGAGUAGAAAAUAUUAAUGAAAUUAAGAAUUGUUGAGAUUAUAUGAAUUGGGCUAGAAUACUAAGGGGAAAACUAUGUUUUGAAUAGAGUUUGGCAUUUUUGACCAAGAACAAAAUUGAGUUUUCAUUGGAAAGAAAGGAAACCUUGAUUCUUACCAUUGCUGCUCCAAAGGAGGCCCAGGUUAAGAGGAUUAGAGGAGACACGCGGUGCUGGGCAUUCCUGGCAGGUGUUGGGUGAUCCCCGCAGUAUGUCACCUGCAGUUGCAGCACAGGCAGCUAGUGAUUGGGUUCAUCUCCUCCUAGUGGUUGGAAGAGAACUCAGAUGUAAAAACCAGCGGUCCUUCUCCCACCUUCUUUCCUGCCAUUCUUGCUCAUCAUACAUGUCCGUAAACUUGAAGAACUCGUUUUAGCAGCUAGCCUUUUAAGGUCGAGGAUGGGAAAGCUAAAACUGUAGAAUAUUAUUAUGCUGCUUUUUAGGUUUAUCCCUGUUGUUGUGGGAUGCAAGUUAAGGGAUUGUAAUUGUUUUUCAGGGUUUUUUUGUUUUUUGUUUUUUAAGCAAGGGCUCUAUUUUCCCUUGAGAGUUCUGGAACUAAGCCUUGGAGAAACACUACUGAGUGUAUUUAGGCUCCCUGGUUUUCUUGCCCAACAACAAUCUGAAGGGUAGGGGGUGGGGGCUGUGUCUUACUCAGGGGCAGCACCUAGCUGUCUUGCCUACAGUGGGUGCACGAUAUAUAAAUGGAAUUGAUUUUUGUCAACACUGUCAAGAGUGGCAUUGACUAUUGGAGCAUACCCCGUCCACAUGAUGCUUGAACUAUGUAACUUCAGGGGUUGAGGGCUCAAGGUUCAGGUUAAAGAGGCACUGUCAACUUACUAUACAAGCAUAAUUUAGGUUUUUCCUUUUUCUACUUGAAAAGGACCAGCUUAAACACAAACCCUUAUGUAAAUUAAAAGGUUUGAAUCCAAAGCAGAGAGAACUGCUUCUGGAAAAGUGUAGUUUAAUUUUAACUAUUCUAAAAGCAAUGAGCAAAGGCCCUUGUCCAAGGCGUUGACAGUUUUCUAAAGUGGUUAUGCUGUAUAUCUGGAUGCAUGCCUUUGGGCUGCCACUGCUUGAUUCCUUUCAUGUACAGAUAAUAUUACUUCAGUUUAGAUUUCCCACUUUAAAAUGCAGUGAUUUGUGUUGAAUACAUCUUGAUUGUGCUUUACCUAAAGUAUUUUCUUAAAAGGCUUUGUGUAAAAUUUAAAUGUAUAUAUUUUCCUGUAGACUUCCAUCAUGAUUUUCAGAGAUUAGCCUUAAAAAAUUUGGCCCUAAGAAAUUCAUUCAGUGUUUUUCUAGAUGACCUCUGUACAUAGAGGUCAUUAUAGUGGAGACCCUUUACCAGCAGCAUUUUAAGAUUUAAAUUAGAUAGAAAGUUUCUUAGGAUUCAACUGAAAAUUGGCUAGUAAAAUAUGUCCCAGGUAAUAAAGCAUGCUGACUUUGCUAAGGCACUGCCCAUUUUUAUUUAACUAAAGUCAUGGAGAUUUUGAGUUUAAAGGAUGCAGUAUAGAUAGUGGUUUAGUGUUUAGGCUCUAAUGCCAGUCUAAAAGGCAAGUCAUUUAACCUUGGGAGCCUCAGUUUCCUCACUGUAAAACAGGGAUAAUAAUAGUAACUACCUCAGGGUUGUUGUAAGGAUUAAAUGAGAUGAUAUUUGUAAGAUACUUAGCUCAAGUGCCUGGCACACAAUGAGCACACUCUAUAAAUGUUCUACUACUACUAUUAUUAACACCUAGUCUAGGGAUGCACAGCAGAAUCCCCUAGGGUUAAAAAACAAAACAAAACAAACAAAAAAAACUGACGGAAUAGCCCCACUCCAGAUCAGAAUUCCCAGUGGGCUGGGGUCUCGGCCAGUGUAUUCUCCAGUAAUCUCGCCAGGUGUUUGAAACACCCAGUGCUAUCUGAAAACUAUCAGUACCCCAACCCUUUGGUUUAUAGAUUAAGAAACUAGCAGAAGAUGGUUAAAUUACUUGCCUAUUGUCUCAGAACGGUUAAUUAGUGGCGGAGCCAAGGCUAGAAUUCAAGUCUCUUGACUUUAUGGUUGUGGGGUCUUUCCACCAUACCUGCUGCCAUGUGAGACACUGCAAAAAAGUGGCUCAGACCGACAAUCAGCCUGUGUGGUGCUGCACACUUUCUAAAGCACAUGCUCCUGACACUUUGACCUUAAGGGGCUUGAAUGUGGAGUAAUGGGAACACAAGCCAAGCAAGCACUCAGUAGAAUUCAGUCAUUUAAAAAAUUCAAUGGGGUCAUUCUUUUGGACAGACCUCAGCAACACAGCAAUGUGCACUUUGUAGUAAAGAAAUACCAACUUGAGUUUUUAAAAAACCUAGUUAGUCCUACAUUCCCUUUUCUUUAAAAAAACUUUAUUGUUCACAUUAUUUUAAUGACUAUGAGAUAAUGUAUAUGACAGCACUUUGAGAAAAUAUCAACUGUAAUAUAACUAUAAGGUUGUAGUAUUGUCUGUUUAAAAGAUAAGACAGUUGAUUCAAUGUGGAUGGACCCUGUGGGGUACCUGAAAAUGUAGAUACGUAAGAAUCACCUCUGUCAUUUAUCACAUUUAGAAAUAUGAAACUGCUUAACAGGUAUGAGCAGGUAUAGCAAGUGUUUGCUAAAGUUGUAGUUCAGAGCUGAAUUACUUCAGGAAACUAGGGACCAACUUUUUGGUUUAAUUCCGAUCUUUAAAAAGUAAGAAUGUGUACUCACUCCAGAACACAGAAGCUCUUCCAAGGACCUUGACUCAAGAAGGAUGAGGUCCUCUUACUCUUCUCCAUUUAUCCACUAUAUGCUUGGCCAUUUAUCCUAAAUGUGGUGGGAACAGACUUGUUAUCUGUUGAUGUUGACAGUGUCUUUUUUAACCUAUGUCCUGCAUAGUUUUGUUAGGUUUACAGGGGGAGGUGGAUGGCCAUAAAACCAGUGCACUUUGGGAAUUACUUUUCUAGGAUUUCCUACCAGUUAUAAAUGACAUUGACAUUUGUCAUCUUUUUUUUCUUUUUCUAAAAAGAAUAGCUGAAUUUAAUUCACCUAUUAUAAAAUACUCAAAAGUAAAUUGCCUUGGUGGCCACUUCUGAAUUAUAGCUACAUUUCAUUAUGACCCCUUCUGCUCCCUUCCAUUUUGCUACUGAUGUCAUUCUUGUUAUCAGGCUGUGCCCCUACCAGGAGUUCAUAUUGGGUUGACAGGGUUAUCUAUAUUUUUGUUCUUGAUUUUUGAGUUUCAUCAUCUUGCAUUAAAUUGUUCCACCUGGAUUUGGGGUUCAUCUCUGUGCCCUAAGGAUCUGCUAUGACCAAUCCUCUUUUUGUAGGUGGGUCUCUGGCUUAAGUAUUGAUAGGCUUCAGCGGUUUGUGUCUCUGUCUUAGCUUGUAUCAAGCCAGUAGUAGCUCACUUCCUUUGUAAAUUCCUGCUUCAGUCUGGGAUCCGUAGGAGUAUGUGAGAACUUCUGAAACGUCUCCAACUCUUAACAGUCAAGAUAUCUAUAUCAUUUGGAUAGAGUUCUGGUUUUCCAACUACUAGACUUAAAGAAAUUCUGGCCGGGUGCGGUGGCUCACGCCUGUAAUCCCAGCACUUUGGGGGGCUGAGGCGGGUGGAUCACGAGGUCAGGAGAUUGAGACCAUCCUGGCUAACACGGUGAAACCCCACCUCUACUAAAAAUACAAAAACUUAGCUGGGCGUGGUGGCGGGCGCCUGUAGUCCCAGCUACUGGGGAGGCUGAGGCAGGAGAAUGGCGUGAACCCAGGAGGCGGAGCUUGCAGUGAGCCCAGAUCGCGCCACUGCACUCCAGCCUGGGUGACAGUGAGACUCCGUCUCAAAAAAAAAAAAAAAAAAAAAAAAAAAAAAAAAAAGAAAUUCUAAUGCAAAGCUUGCUUUUUUUUUCUUUUUUCCAGCAAGCCAGUAGUAAUAGUUAUUGUUACUUGCUCUGUUCAGCACAACUGUAGUUCACUUGAACUUCACUGUCAUUCCCUACGCUCCUCUCUUACUGAGAAGCAUGGGUGGGAUUCAGGGCUGUGGGACAAGCUACAGCCUACUCUGGAGCACUCACCCCCAUGACUCAGUCCAGCCUGUCUCUUGGGAAGUUUAUUGCAAUGUGCAGACGGAUGAAUUUCUGCUUUUCAUGCCACCUCUCUGAGGUAUGUAUUCUAUCUUGAGUAUGUACAAGAUGAUACCUUUUGGCUGGGCACAGUGGCUCGUGCCUGUAAUCCCAGCACUUUGGGAGACCAAGAUGGGCGGAUCACUUGAGGUCAGGAGUUUGAGACCAGCCUGGCCAACAUGGUGAAACCCCGUCUCUACUAAAAAUAUAAAAAUUAGCCGGGCGUAGUACAUGCCUGUAAUCCCAGCUACUCCCGAGGCUGAGGCAGAAUUGCUUGAACCCAGGAGGCGGAGGUUGCAGUGAGCUGAGAUCGCGCCGCUGCACUCCAGCCUAAGUGACAGAGUGAGACACGUUAAGAAGAAAAAAAAAAAAAAGGAUACCUUCAUUUCUGACUCAAUAUCCUAGAUCCAAAGGACAGGAAAUUAGGGAAGGCUUCACCCUGUGGGAUCAAGAUAAGAAGAUCCCAUACUUCUUCCCAGGUAAGGAGGCCUGUGGCAGGUCAUGAUUCAAAGCUGACUUGGAAUGGCAGAAACUGCUGAGAGGCCACCCUUGGAGAUUUGUGCCUUCAAAGAUGGGUUUCAUGAGUCUCAGAGAGGAAAAGACUUGUCAGCUGGGUUGAUUUUGCAUGAUUAUUGAACUAGAGCUGGUAGACACGAGCUUCUCAGAUGGCAGUGGCCAGAUCCUCCAUCUGUGAGAAUCCGCCACUUGAAGUGGUUUCCUGAGAGUGUUCACUUGGCAGUUGCUGCGUUUCUCAAGCCCACCUGGCGAGGUCUCGCCGGACCCUUCCCUCCAAGUGCACUUACUUCUUCAUCCCCAUGUACAUCUCUAACUUUGAAAUUGUUUACCUCUCCUACAAAAAUCUUACCUUUUGACCUGAGCAGAGUAGCAAAGCCCUGUUCACUCUGAGGGAGCAGCUGGCGUGUUGAAGGGGAAAGGCCAGGCACAGCACUGUCCUCAGACCACACCAUAUUUGGAGCAGAAUUGUGAUACAUGUCAUCUGUGUCUAUUCUGGAAGGUUCUUUGUUCAUCACUGUACUCGCAUCAGCAAAUUUUCAGGGUCCUACCUGUCACUCCAGGCUACUGAGCUGAACCCUCAGAAGCUGAGGUCUCCGAGCAUGCUAAGUAACCUUUUAGAAAAGCUGGAGGCAAACUGUCGAAUGCUAGCAGGCUUUAUGAAAGGAAACAUAAGGAGUUUGUGUAGUCAGAACUUGCUUAAAUUUGCUUCGGAAUUAGGCACCAUAAACUUUAGUUGGAGAAUGGGACUUAAAUUUUCACAUAUAUGUAUACUUAAUUUUCAGCAAUUAUGACACAAUAAAAAGAAUAUGCAAAUUUAUUGUUGUUUCAGAAGGUUUUGCAGGACUGGGAACGCUUUAGUGUCAUCAACAGUAAACCUCAGAUACUGUUCUGCACAGUUCAGAAGUACCAUACCAGGUAUUGUGAGUGGCAAGAACGCCAGGGGACAGAGAUGCUUCUGGUAGAUGAGGGCCAGAGAAACCAGCUCUCCUCCAUUUUGACAGCAAUUUCUCACUGUGGCCAUUUGGCCUCCAUUAUGUUUUGAGAGGAAUUUCUUGAGAUCUUGAGAAAUCACCAUGAUUAGGCCAAUUGUCAAUCAGUAUUCAGAAACUAGAAAGGAACAAUGAGAUACUUGUUUAUGGUUCUUUAGGGCAUAUGUUUGAAAACCCUCUCAUCUCAGAUCUGUAUAGCUGGUGUGUGUUUGUGUCCAUAAAUACACGUGCAUUGCUGUCGUGCCCAUUAAGAAAGGGGGAGUAAGUAAAAGAGGAAUCGCUCAGAUCUUUCCUUGGAUGAACAGCAGUGGCGUGGUUGGUGUGUUGACUGUGAACAGGCUGACUUAGCUGUUGAUGUAUACUCAGAACCUCCAUCUCCUCCCAGACCCUGCACUUUUCCUUCUCUGCAGUCUGAUUCUCUAAUGACUGUCACUGGACAAACCCCAGUUUUAUGCUCGCUUAGUAAAAAUAAGUUUAAACAUUUCAUGGUGGUUGACAGAACUUUGUCCCCAAACAUGCGGAUUCAAUUCUUUAAAACUCGUUGAACGUUUAUACCAAAGGUCCCGCCCCGCAGGUGUGUAUGUGGUGCACAGAGGGUGAGGUUUGGAGCAUCGGGCACUGUGUGCAUUGCUAAGGGGACAUAGUGAGACAAUGUGGGAUUUAACUAAAAACACAUCAAUUGUGUGUCACAUUACCAGUGUUGUCAGGUAUUUGUUCUUAAUUGUUAUUGUAAUAUAUUUUCAGUUGUUUUUCUAAUUUAAUUCUCUCCGUCUGUUGUCUGACUGUGAACUGCUAACAGUGUUAAACUUGAUGUAAAUAAAUGAGGCCCUUGAAAGGGACUGCUUUCUCUGUCUUCUCACAAGGUUUGCCAAGUUGUGUUCUGUUUUAAAUAAAGGUUGCAAUAUUUUAUUGGCAAA